AGGGAUUCCCAAGUCCCAGCGAUUCCCCCACUUCCUCUCCACCUGCCACAGCUGCCAGCGACCGCCCGCCUGAAACCACUGCCAUUUGGACAGCAUGCCAGGCCACCCAGGAGCAGCUGAGCAACUUGUCAAGACCGGGUGGAGGUCCUGGCACUUGGGGUUCUGGAAGGCCCUUGCCCCACUGCAGGCUGCCUGGGACGCCUUCUCCCAGCCUGUUCCAGCCAGCUGUGGCCAGCUGCUGACCCAGCUCCUCCUGUGUGCCUCCCUGGCUGCUGCUGCUGCAGGUCUGGUUUAUCACUGGCUGGCAUCCUUGCUGCUUUAUCCUCCUGGACCUUCAGCCAUGGUUGCCACUGUCUGUGGCCUCCUGGUCUUCCUGAGCCUGGGCCUGGUACCCCCAGUCCGCUGCCUGUUUGCACUCAGCGUGCCCACCCUGGGUAUGGAGCAGGGCCGCCGGCUGCUCCUGUCCUACAGCACUGCCACCCUGGCCAUUGCUGUGGUGCCCAACGUCCUGGCCAACGUGGGUGCGGCCGGGCAGGUGCUGAGGUGUGUCACCGAGGGCUCCCUGGAGAGUCUCCUCAAUACCACUCACCAGCUGCAUGCAGCAUCCAGGGCUCUGGGCCCCACAGGCCAGGCAGGCAGCCGGGGCCUGACAUUUGAGGCCCAGGACAAUGGCUCUGCCUUCUACCUUCACAUGCUCAGGGUCACUCAGCAGGUCCUGGAGGAUUUCUCUGGCCUGGAGUCCCUGGCCCGGGCAGCAGCGCUAGGGACCCAGCGAGUGGUCACAGGGCUGUUUAUGUUGGGCCUCCUGGUGGAGUCGGCAUGGUACCUCCAUUGCUACCUGACAGACCUGCGGUUUGACAAUAUCUACGCCACUCAACAGCUGACCCAGCGGUUGGCACAGGCCCAGGCUACACACCUCCUGGCCCCUCCACCCACCUGGCUGCUCCAGGCGGCUCAGCUGAGGCUGUCACAGGAGGAGCUGUUGAGUUGUCUUCUAAGGCUGGGGCUGCUUGCCCUGCUCCUCGUGGCCACGGCUGUGGCGGUGGCCACAGACCAUGUAGCCUUCCUCCUGGCACAGGCUACUGUGGACUGGGCUCAGAAGUUGCCAACUGUGCCCAUCACGCUCACGGUCAAGUAUGAUGUGGCAUACACUGUCCUGGGCUUCAUCCCUUUCCUCUUCAACCAGCUGGCUCCGGAGAGCCCCUUCCUCUCCGUCCACAGCUCCUACCAAUGGGAGCUCCGCCUCACCUCCGCCCGCUGCCCACUGCUACCCGCCCGGCGUCCCCGCGCAGCUGCCCCGCUGGCCGCGGGGGCCCUGCAGCUCCUGGCGGGCUCCACGGUGCUCCUGGAGGCCUACGCCCGCCGCCUGCGGCAUGCCAUCGCCGCUUCCUUCUUCACAGCCCAGGAGGCGAGGAGGGUCCGCCACCUGCACGCCCGGCUCCAGCGAAGACACGACAGGCACCAAGGCCAGCAGCUGCCCCUAGGGGAUCCUUCUUGCGUCCCCACACCCAGACCUGCCUGCAAGCCUCCGGCAUGGAUAGACUACAGGCUGGAUGCCUUAAGAACCGAGAGCAGUGAGGGAGAAGGGAAAGAGCUUUGGAGUUGCAGAGACCUGAGUUGUAACCUUGGUCCUGUGCCGCCUCCCUGUGUGACCUUGGGUAAGUCACUUCACCUCUCUGAGCCUCGGUUUCUACAUCUGCAUAACGACAGCAUAUUUACCAUUGAUGUGACCUACUUCCCACGCAGGGAUGUGGUCAGGAUGGAAGGAAAUACUGGGCAUGAUAGGCCUGGAUAACCGGUAAAGAACCAUGCAAAGGCGAAGACAAGGAGUGCAGAGAGAGCUCAUGGUUCCUCCAGGCUGGUUGGCGAUCAGGCUCAUCUCAUCUGCACCAACUGCUCUACUUGUUAGAUGGAGACCUUGCAUCAUGAAUUUCUCGAAAUGCUCCUGGAACUUAUUUAUAUGCCUCAAAAUCCUCUAAACUCAUUUAUAGUAACCCAUAGUUUUAAUUUUAUAAAUAAACGUAUUUAUUAAAUCUUAGAUUACGUUAUUCCUCUGCCUCAAAUUCCUUCAGGGCCUUUCCAUUGCCAGGAUUAGAUUUUGCCAAAUUAAAAUAUAGGACACU